AGCUGUCGCCGGCGGCCGGCCGGCGGUCAGCCUUCACACAGGCCCGGCUGCGGAGCGCAGUCGCCCAGGUUUACGGCGGCAGAGGGCCGAGGCUCCCGGAGAGGACCGCGAUGAGUCCACUUCAGGUCGGGGCUGAGUGUGGGCGCGCGGUUCCCGGCGGCGUGUGACCCAGUCUUCGCCGGCCGCUGCCCGCUGCGUGUGUAAGUGUCCGUGGGCCCCAGGGCCUUGCAGCGCCCGCCCCGAGGCCCCGAAGAGGCCUUCCGCCUGGGGCAGUGUGAAGGCCACAGAGUUUUCCUCCAAAGCCACACCUCAGCUGGAAGGGGCGAGUUGGAGGGCUCUGUUAGUGGUAGCCAUGGGGAGACGCGGAGCUGCAGCUGUCGCUUUGCAGUGCCUGUAGGACUUUGAGGGCCUGGAGCCCCGGUUCCCUGAACAGCACCCAGAUCGCCCCAUAUCUGAGACACAGUUCAUGCCCCCCUUCCCUAACUCUGAAGUAAAAUCUUGAGGGCUGUCAUCUGGGGAAGCCACCUUGUCCGUUCAGCCAUGAAGACAGAAACAGUGCCACCGUUCCAGGAAACUCCAGCUGGAUCGAGCUGUCACCUCAAUAACCUGUUGAGUAGCCGGAAGCUGAUGGCUGUGGGGGUCUUGCUUGGCUGGCUCCUGGUCAUACACCUUCUGGUCAACGUGUGGCUGCUGUGCCUUCUGUCGGCAUUGCUAGUGGUGCUGGGAGGAUGGCUGGGCUCCAGCCUCGCUGGAGUGGCUUCAGGUCGACUGCAUCUGGAACGCUUCAUCCCGUUGGCCACCUGUCCUCCAUGCCCUGAGGCAGAAAGGCAGCUGGAACGGGAGAUCAACCGCACCAUCCAGAUGAUUAUUCGAGAUUUUGUGUUAUCUUGGUACCGUUCCGUGAGCCAGGAGCCAGCCUUUGAGGAAGAAAUGGAGGCAGCCAUGAAAGGGUUGGUCCAGGAGCUUCGGAGAAGGAUGAGCGUGAUGGACAGUCAUGCUGUUGCCCAGAGUGUUCUGACUCUCUGCGGUUGUCACCUGCAGAGCUACAUUCAGGCAAAGGAGGCCACUGCAGGGAAGAAUGGUCCAGUUGAGCCUUCCCACCUCUGGGAGGCUUACUGCCGGGCGACUGCCCCACAUCCUGCUGUGCACAGCCCCAGUGCUGAAGUCACCUAUACGCGUGGCGUUGUGAAUUUGUUGCUUCAAGGGCUGGUGCCCAAGCCCCACUUGGAGACUCGUACCGGACGCCAUGUAGUGGUCGAACUCAUCACAUGCAAUGUAAUCUUACCACUGAUCAGCAGGCUGUCAGAUCCUGACUGGAUCCACCUUGUACUCGUGGGUAUCUUUUCCAAGGCCAGAGAUCCAGCACCCUGCCCAGCCAGUGCCCCCGAACAGCCCUCAGUGCCGACAUCUCUGCCACUGAUUGCUGAGGUAGAGCAGCUUCCAGAAGGGAGAGCUUCUCCAGUAGCAGCCCCAGUAUUCCUAAGUUACAGUGAGCCAGAGGGUUCUGCAGGCCCCUCUCCAGAGGUUGAAGAAGGCCACGAAGCUGUAGAGGGAGAUUUGGGUGGGAUGUGUGAAGAAAGAAAAGUAGGAAACAACUCAUCUCAUUUCCUACAGCCAAAUGUUCGAGGUCCCCUGUUCUUAUGUGAAGACUCAGAGCUGGAGUCUCCGCUGUCUGAACUGGGCAAAGAAACCAUCAUGCUCAUGACUCCAGGCAGCUUUCUCUCUGACAGGAUUCAGGAUGCCCUGUGUGCCCUAGAGAGUUCCCAGGCUCUGGAACCCAAAGAUGGUGAGGCAUCUGAAGGAGCAGAGGCUGAGGAGGGUCCAGGGACAGAAACAGAGACAGGCCUGCCGGUCUCCACACUGAAUUCCUGCCCAGAGAUCCAUAUUGACACAGCAGACAAGGAGAUAGAACAAGGAGAUGUUACCGCCUCUGUUACAGCUUUGCUGGAGGGGCCAGAAAAGACCUGCCCCUCACGGCCGUCAUGCUUAGAGAAGGAUCUCACCAAUGAUGUGAGCUCCCUUGAUCCUACUCUGCCACCAGUUCUGCUUUCCUCCUCUCCACCUGGUCCUCUCAGCUCAGCCACCUUCAGCUUUGAGCCCCUAAGCAGUCCCGAUGGUCCAGUUAUCAUCCAGAACCUUCGUAUCACUGGCACCAUUACAGCCCGAGAGCACAGUGGCACUGGAUUCCACCCAUACACACUCUAUACUGUGAAGUACGAGACAGCCCUUGACGGUGAAAACAGCAGCGGCCUGCAGCAGCUGGCCUACCACACUGUGAAUCGUCGCUAUCGGGAGUUCUUGAAUCUGCAGACCCGUCUGGAGGAGAAACCAGAUCUACGAAAGUUCAUCAAAAAUGUGAAGGGUCCUAAAAAGCUCUUUCCAGAUCUUCCAUUGGGAAACAUGGACAGUGACAGAGUAGAAGCCCGUAAGAGCCUCCUAGAAUCAUUCCUAAAGCAACUCUGUGCCAUUCCGGAGAUCGCUAACAGUGAGGAGGUGCAGGAGUUCCUUGCUCUGAACACAGAUGCUCGUAUUGCCUUUGUCAAGAAACCAUUUAUGGUCUCUAGAAUAGACAAGAUGGUGGUGAGUGCCAUUGUGGACACCUUGAAGACAGCGUUUCCUCGCUCUGAACCCCAGAGCCCCACAGAGGAGCUGAGUGAGGCCGAGACCGAAAGCAAGCCCCAGACAGAAGGCAAGAAGGCUAGCAAGUCUAGGCUGAGGUUCUCAUCCAGUAAAAUUUCUCCAGCACUAAGUGUGACUGAAGCACAAGACAAGAUUCUUUAUUGUCUCCAGGAAGGCAAUGUGGAGUCUGAGACUCUAUCCAUGUCUGCGAUGGAAUCUUUUAUUGAAAAACAGACAAAGUUACUGGAAAUGCAGCCAACAAAAGCCCCAGAAAAAGAUCCUGAACAACCUCCCAAAGGACGUGUGGACAGUUGCGUGUCAGAUGCAGCCGUGCCAGCCCAAGACCCCAGCAACAGCGAUCCAGGAACAGAGACAGAGUUAGCUGACACAGCCCUGGAUCUGCUCCUCUUGCUACUAACAGAACAGUGGAAAUGGCUAUGUACCGAAAACAUGCAAAAGUUUCUUCGUCUUAUCUUUGGGACCCUAGUUCAAAGAGUUCUAGGGUUCUGCAGAAGUGCUUCUGAAGCCAACUUAGAAGCUCAGGGAAAACUGAGUGGACCAUGACCCAACCACAGAAGUUACACUUUGAUCAGUUUAAUAUACUGGGGCUCUAGGUAACGCUUUGUUUGAAAAGGGGCUCCACUCUGUUUAAAAUAUGCAUUUAUUUCUUUAUAUUAAAAUUCCACCUCCUUUCUUACUUGGCAUGAUCUGGUUUCAGUCUUAUUUUUCAUUUUCCACCGUGUAAACGUCCAUCAUUGCCUGAAUAUUCUGUGGUCUUUUACCCCCAGGCCUUUGCUCAUCUUCCUGUAUCUGCCUUCGAAUGGUCUUUCUCUACCUGUUAUUUCCCUGUUCCUUCCAUGUGUUCCUAACUUUUCCUCUUCUUGUCUGCUUGGCCUACUGCAAAACAUUUUUCAUAUAUUAAGCAUAAAAUGUCAUUUAUUCUGUGAAACCUUCUGUAGCAUCUGCUCUCUUUCCCCGAGAAUUAAGGAGUCCUCUUCUCUAACUUGCAAAGUUUUGAUAAUAAUACUUGUCACAGUGUGUUUAUAUAAAUGAUCUGCUUUUCCUACACUAGUGGUUGUCAACUGGGGUACACUUUUGUCCCCCAGGGGACACUUGCCAUUAUCUGGAGAUAUUUUUUGUUGUCACAACUGGGAAGGAGAUGUGGGAUGCCUACUGGCAUCUAGUGGAUGUAGGCCAAGGAUGCUGCUAAACAUCCUGCAGCUACACAGGACAGUCCACCAUGCCAAACAACGUGAAUUAUCCUGCCCAAAAUAUCAGUGUUACCAAGCUUGAGAAAUGCUGUGUAGACUAUUAGUUCUUUAAGGACCGGAACUAGCUUUGUCUCCCCAGCAGCUUAUACAGGGCCUGGACAUAGUAGGUACUCAUUAAAUAUUGAAUAAAGAAAUAAACAUUUCCCUUCCCAGUACCUUUACACUUGAAAGUAUAGUCUCUUUAGUUUUAUUCUGUCACCUCUGGAUGUCACUAAUUAGGCCUUCAUUUCUCUUCUUCUUUUUUUGGACUUCCCUUUGCUAAUCUUCUAAGUGGUUUAAAAAAACAAAAUGAGAAGAUCCCAAAACUAGCUAGUGUGUGAUCUAAUAUGACCCCUUCUCCUUGAGGUCAUUUACAUGACAGAUUGGUUUCAGAACACGAGAAAUUAUUCAGUAUGAGGAUAAAAGUAUAGAUGAGUUAGGAGAAAUUCAAAAAAGAUUGAGAUCCUUAUAUAAAAGGGGUAGGAAAAAGUUGACCUGAAGUUUGAAUAACUCAGAGUGCUCAAGGGUUUGGGCUAGUCCAGAUAAAGGAGAAAUACCUAUAUUCUGGGAGUUAGAGAAUGAUCACAGAAGUACUUUUUCAUGUGGCCGGGGCCCUGGGAGAUCUAAGGCAGAAAAGUUAAAUACGAGCGAAGCAAGCUCCAGCUGCGUGGCAGACAUGGAAAAGACAGGGCUCAUUUUAGAGUUCAGAGCAGAGGCUGUGAGACUUCUUUCUUUUUCAUUUUUCAUAUAUUGAGGAUAAAAUGUCAAUAUAUGAAAUAUCAGUGAGAUGGGAUUUCAUUCUGUCGCCCAGGCUGGAGUGCAGUGGCACUGCAAUCAUAGCUCACUGUAACCUCCUGGGCUCAAGCCAUCCUCCCACCUCAGCCUCCCAGGUAGCUAGGACUACAGGCACACACCACCGUGCUUGGCUAAUUUUUUAAAUUUUUUGGUUGAGAUGGGGUCUCACUAUGUUGCCCAGGCAAGUUCCUCACCUUUCCAUUCCUGUCCCUGACACUCCCCAACUACAACCACAACUCCAGUGAGCUGGGUAAAGUCUGGUGAAUGCAGACUAGCAAAACCCAAAUGUAGCUCAUGCCAUAAAGGAAAUGAGGGAGAGGGCUUACAGCUGAAUUUCCCUAGACUUUCUCCUCUUUUCACAUUCUGACUUUUUGUUUUUUGGUUUUGUCUUAUUCUGUUUUAUGGAAAAGCAUCACUAUUGUGAUGGGAAAAGUGGGAAAACUCUGAAUAUAUUUGGUGAAUUUGAAUGAAGCCACUGUGAAUAUUGGGCAAGAACAGCAUUUUGCGGCUAGUUACUUUUGAAAAACUUGUUGUAACUAUGGCCUGUUAUCUUUGGUUCAUUGUACAUAUUUCCAGGUGAAGAUGUUUUAUACAUGUUCAGUUACCUCAUAUCCCUUCCUGUCAACAAGUUCUUAUAUCUAAGAAUACAACUUUAUCCUUAGCCCAUUUGGUUUUGUAUUAGCUGCAAUGAAAAUAGGACCACAUCUGGUUAGCAGUCUCCUCACCCAAGCUUCCACAGACUAGAAUUAAAUGAAGAAUCUCAUACUUCUCUGUUUGAGGCCAUUCAUGUAUCCCUACAAAUCAUUUUUCCCAUCUUUUUAAUGACAUUUUUGGCCCUCUUCUGAAGUACCUUAUAGCUGGUUUCACAGUUUUCCUGAAGCCUCCUUAAGAUAGGAAGCUAGAAGUCAUGAUAUCUAAAGAAAGAACCGGUUCUUCCACUAGAGCUUCCAAAGAUCUGGCACUGGUGGCCCAUGGUCUCAUACCUGGAAGCACCCUGUGCAUUAUAGACAUGGAGCUAACACAUUUUAGCAUUCAGAGUGUAAACGUUGAUAAUCUCGUCAGCAUCAGCACAUUUGCUGUCCAGCAAAUGUUUAUCGAGAGUUGACUUAGUGCAAAUACUGUACUGAACACUGUAUGCACAUGCUGUUCAAAAGCCACAGUUACUUUUGCACCAACUUAAUACCAUUUAAUUCCUCCAAGUCCUGCGAAAGCGGUACUAUGACCCUCAUUUUAAAGACAAGGAAACUAAGGUUUACAAAGAAUGUGGGUUAUCUAGUCAAAAUCACAGGGUUAAUAAAUAUCACAAGCAGAAUUUGAACCCAGGUUUUUCUGAUUUAUAGCUGUGAUGAUUGUCUAAAUUUCAGGAUCAGAUCUUUGCCCUGCAAUUCAGCAGGAUAAAAGCCAACCCAAAAAUCUCUGUCUCCAAGUACUGGAGAUUAUCAGGCAGUUUGUAGAAUCCAAACUGCAUCUCCGUAUCUACACACUUGCAGCUAACCUAAGGGCAGUGCUGCAGUCUAAAGACAGCCCAUGUUACUAUCCCUGGGACAGUUGCAGGUUUUAAUUUUAAAAAGUGGUGUAUGCAUUGCUGCAUGCUUCAGCUUUAUUUGCUUUGGUAAGCCAAUAUGCUGGAAACUUGACAUCUCCAGAGCUGCAGCACCUCUCCACUGUACCCCCUGCAUCUCCCACAAGAGGCAUGAUAUGAGGUCCCGUUGCCUCCCAUCCCCAUGACUGCUGCCUAGGAGGCUACAUGUUUGUCCUCCCUGAAACCACGGGUAGCUGAGCCAUAUGCUUUUGCAGGGUACUUGGGUUCUCUUCCUUUAAGUUCCGUGCUUAAAAGAGCAGGAUAGUUGGUGUUGGUGCCACACGUGGUACUGCCACUUCUCUAGUUAUUUAGAACUCACUGCAGUUUGACCAUCAGGGAUGCUGUAGUCACCAGAUUUGAGUGCAUCUCCUCCUUAAAAUGUCCUCAUGUUCCAACCUCCAGUAUUAUUAUCCCCAAGCAGGCAAGUUUAUUCCUCUGCUUCCAACUUUGUAUACCCAUCUUGCAACUUUAAAAGACCUGUGUACAUUACUGCCUUGGACGCCAUAGACUUCUGUCAAAUUAUAAGCACACUCUCUAUCCUGCAAAGGAAAAAAAAAAAACAGAGUAAGUUCGACCUCAUAACCCCUCCUUCUAAGCCAAAGUUGGAAGAGCUCUGAUCUGAGCCAGGCUUAUAAAUCUCCGUUGAUUGUUGAUGAUGUGGAGAGAAGUGGGAGGGGAGCUGAAGAGAAGUUAGAUGCCCAAAAAAGGCAUUGUUAAGUCAAAGGGAAGUCUUGCAUGCAUGUGCGCCUAACCUCAUGUGUCAGCUUCUGUGCUGGGAACAUCCAAUUAUGUAACAAGAAGCACUCCUUAUUUGGAAUGAGAGACAAAGGGAGGGGAAGGGGAGAGCGGGUAGCACUCUGAGCCAAGGAGCAAAUCCGGCUUGUGCAAACUCUGCUCAUGCCCGAAAACAGAAGAAACUUGAAAAUAUCUCUGCAAACAUCAGAAUCAGAUUUAGCAAACUGGGCAAGUACUCAGAGUUAGACUGGGUUGGAGGGAAAGAGGAGAGAUACACUGUGCUGCAUUGAUGGUAGGGGGUUUGGGGCAGGAAGAUCCAGCCAAGGUAAGGGGUAGGAUUGGUGUGGAGUCCUGAUGGAAAGUGAAGGAAUGAGAAGCUGGACCGGCGCCCUGCCUGGACACCCAGAGCAAUGCCACGAUAAAAAUAGGAACCAUGCCAGCAGCAGAAUGCGUGAAUGCCACGUCCGCGGCGCUGCCCUCCCCAUGGCCCCAACGAUGGCAUCAGACCUGUGUCAAAAGGGCAGCAGACACAUUCCUGGCAUCUGCGUCAGGAUUUCUCAGUUAAAAAGGGAGUGUGUGUGUGUGUGUCUGUGUGUGUGUGUGUAAGAUAGAGACAGAGUGUGUGUGUGUGAGUGUUGGGGGCAUGUGGGAAUGGAAUGGCUUGGCAGAAAGCCAGGGGGAAAGGUUCUGGCAGAGGGGAGCGUGAAGUGUGUAAAGUUAGGAAGUAUCCAGAGAGGAAGAAGAAAAGAAAGGGUGUGCAGGUUUAAGGAGUCCAACAAGCAGGGCACCCAGGAGAAACUUGAUGGCAAGCUCUAGACCUUACACCAGACCUUGGAAUCACUUUCUUAGAGAAGAUGUCUCUCUCUAAACCAUCUCCUAGGAAAGGUCAGGAGAGCUGCGGCAGAGUCUGGGAGCACUGGAGAGUGCUGUGCUGCAAGGCGCAACGUCCACCUCCCCUAAGGACAGUUGGGAAAGGUUGACCAUGAACCCUCUUGCUUCCACUGUUCUCUUAGAACGCUCCAGAAUCAAGGCGCUUUCUGUGGAACUCUACUUCAAGGGCCUCUUUCUUGGUGGGCAUGUCUAACUAGCAGGUGGAUAACAGUUCUUUGUGACAUUGGUUAUUUCUUAAGAGAACCUCCAGGUCUGCCACCAAAAGUGCACGAGUAAUUGCAAUGGGAAAGGAACUGACGCUUAUUACAAUAUUAAUACCAGGAAAGCAGCUAUGUACUGUUUAUAUUAAUGUUCAAUUCUAUGAGAUAGACAUGUAGUUCUACAUUUCAUAAGUGAAGAAAAUUACAUUCAGAUAAAAUAACGUUCCCAAAAUCAUAAAAGUCGUAACAACCACACCUUAAGAUUCCACUUAAGUCAUCCUGGCCUCAGAGCUCAUGUGUUUCCCACUGCUCUGCCAUGCUUCCCCUCCAUGCAAGCUUUCCCACAAAGCAGUGGCCACUAGAACUGGGUUCACCUGAAAGUUCCCUUGCCGUAUUCCCAUCUAGCCUCUCUUGCUUUCCAUCCAGCUGGUCUCAGGGACACACGCAUCUGAUGGUAGCAUAUAAAUUAUUUUUGUCUGCAUAUUCUGAUUUUAUUUUUAAAGCACUUCUGAGCCAGAGAUUGUCUCUUAGCUAUCUCUAUUUAUAUGCUAUUCACAAUCAGGAAAAGAUUAUCAACGUUAAGACUCAGAGUUUCUCAGGAAGCAUAGAUUACAGUUUUUUCCUUUGCUGUGUAACUUUUUCUUCCAGUUCAGCUCUGAUGCCUGGCUAUGUCUUAUACCCCAUCUCUUCCUAUGCACAGCUUUUCUAGAAAUACGCAUACUUUUGCAAGACCCCCACAUACAAAAUUAACUCAAGCUCAGUCUUCAGAAUUCUCGCUUAUUUUCUGGCUCUCCAGUCAUUGGCUUGGGCUGUUUUUAGAGGUGCUGAAAUUAAUUUUUCUCAUUGAUGGCUUUGCUCAGAUUGUACUGUGGCUCCCUGGGAAGGAGUACUGCUUGUCCCAGGCCUCUUCCAUUAGGCCAUGCCAAAGGGAAGCUCUUGACUUCUAUAGACUGGGCCAGGAUGGGCCCUAGCAGUUUCCCCUGUCAUAUGAGUGGUCUGCCUGUCAUAUUUCUUGGGUAUCACUUAUUCUACACCCAUCUUAGGAUGAAGACAUCAUGGCUUUCCUGUCACAUAGUGACAGUCUCUACUGGAAUAUAUCUUUGAGAUUGUAGCAGGUGGAUGGCAGCUGACAGCCGUGUGCCUGAGCAUUGCAUUUGCAUUUCUGUGUGUGUGUGCUCUUGAAGUCUCAUAUACUCAAAUAGAGGUACAAAAUUGCUCAUUGUAAAAGUUAACAAAAAACAGAAUAUCAUGAGGUAUUUAAACCUCAGAGCCUUUUUUUCCAAGUCAGGUUCUUGGCAUCUCUUGCCCAUCUGUGACUGCAAACAGGAACCUAAGAUUUUGACAUUUUGAUGACAGCUUUAGAAUGUAUGUCAGCAUCCUGAGGGCAGGGACUGCGUCUUAUUUACCAUUAUAUCUUCAACACCCAGCCCCAUGCAUAGAAGGCACCUAGUAAAUUUGUGUCAAAUAAAUGAACACAGAAGAUCACACGUCAUUCUACUGGAGGCAGUCCCUCUGCUUAUCACUAUUAAGAAUCUUAGGGUUUCCUCAACAGUGCUGGGGGACCAGAAGCAAAAUGGAAACUGAGUCUUUCAUUCCCUCCACACAGGGCAUACCCAGAUCUUCAGUUAAUUGGGGAAUUCUGAUUCCCAGAGCCAUGGUACGGCCUAAGCAAAGAGGUUUGGGGGCCCUUCAGGCCAUCUCCCAUUCUAAUGGCUCUCUCCUUUCCAAAGAGUGCAGCGCCCCUCCACAACCUGGGCCUCCCAGUAUGAAGCCCCACCGAGCCUGCCCUCUCUGGAAGCAUCUCCUGCUGUUGUACUUUCUCCACCUCUUUCCUUCCACAUGGAAAGCAAGAACUUGGACUUUGAAGUCAGAUCUGAAAUCAGAUCUUGCUUUGAGGCUAUGUGACUUAGAACAAACCACUUAACUUCCUUUGUCUGUUACUGUCGAAAUAGAAAUCAUAGCCUAGUGCAUGAAGUUCUUUGGGGGGAUAAGAGAUAAUUUAGAGGUAAAUGUUAGAGAGGCUUUAUAGAGGAAGGUAUAACAGCUAGAUCUUGUGAGAUAGGUGUCAUUUAGACUGGUUUAGGCUAAAUAAUAUUCUAGACACUAAGACAUUUUUAAAACAGGAGGAGGGGCAUUCUACUUUCAAAUAAAAAGCAACCUGGAAUAUUUUUAGCCAGCUUCUUUCUGAAUGUGUGUUGCUUUUAUUGUUUCAAAUAGGUGACAAAAAGCCUACCAAACUGCUGCUGCAUGGCGUGGGCACAGGAAUUCUCUCUAUGGGCACCAGGUGGCGCUGCAGGUUAAACAAUACCAUUCACUGUCCUUUGAGGAAGACCUGUUUGUUUUGCAGUUAUAGGUCCCCUGCCGUGAUGUUGAUACAGUAUAUUGAAGCCAUUCCCUGGCUUGCUCUACGGUUUAGAGGCCACUUAUCUGCCUACUCCUUAGUGCCAGUGACUUUUAGAUAAGCCCUGUUUCUUUGAUCUUUCACCCUUCUUCCUUCUGCUCUAAUGCGUCUUCAGCAUAUGCUUGCUUCUCUGAGUGGUGUGGAUGACCAGAAGUUGCCCCUUUGAGUGGAUCCCACCCGUUAAAAAUUCAGUGCUGGAGCUGAUUCAUUCAGAACAGAGUGAGCAGAACAGAGUCUGUGGUGAUGAGACCAGCUAGACAUCUGAAUUGCAAGAAUUUUGUUAAUAUUCUGUAUAAACUACUUGGACCUAUAUUCAGGGUCUCCUGUGAUCCUAAAAUCUUAUACAUUAUGUAUUCACUAAGAUGGAGAUUGUCAGUGCUGAAUAGCCCCGAUGUUAGGAAUCUUAUCAACCUGUUACAUAAUCAAGGACAUUCCCUAUUGCUUUCGGCCAUGGAUGGAGACCGUUUGGCUCUCCCCCAUUAACUUGGUUUUGGAGAAGCAACCAUAUGUUAUUGCUUACUUUUGAUCUUUACCUCUGUCCUUGCAGGCUUCUCCAAGUGCCCUUUGGAGAAGUAGAGCUAUUUGGUACUGGAGCAGGGAGGGAGUUGGGUAAAUUGGUGGGAAAUAUACUUUAGCUCUAAUAUAAUGCUGGCCCCGAAAGAUUUCUCGGAGAGGAUUCAGCCUUCCUGGGAGGGAGGCUGGUGUGCAAAUGCAGCAUCAAGGUAAGUUCCUCAACACCUGCCUCCUCUCUCCCCCAGGUUUCCUUUUUGUUGUUUUUCCAGUUUUAUUUAUUACUCCUCUGUGUUUUCUACCCAUAGUCAGUGCUCCCAAAGUUCCUAUUCUGUGGAGAUUCUGGAGUUGCCACUUCGGUGUCCCUACGUCCUUCAUAACGGGAUAGAUGGCCUUCUACUUGGAAAGGUUUUACAUUUCAGCCUGUAGACAGGGAACUGGAAAUACUUUUGGGUAGCUCUUCUACACCAAGGUGAUGGUGUUAAUGAUAGUCACUUUUCCUUCUCCUCUACACCCCUCUCAGUGUUUUUUCUCUUUGUUUAUCUUGGGCAUCUGCUUCUCAUAUAUGUAUUCUUUAUUCUCCUCAAGGCUGGUCUUUUCCAGCCUCCUGUAGCCAUUUUCACAGCAUAAUUUGAAGUCCUCCCAUGUCUGCUGAUUUAAAUAAAUCCCUAAUAAUUUUCUUCCAAAUCAUGGCUGAGCACACUCUAAAUCUGUUAUCCGUAAUAUUUGCAGAAAUUUGGAGGUCAGCCCCUUCUGCGAGCACAUAAUUACUUAUCACUUCUGCCUCCUGCAACCCUUCCCUUCCCAUCCUCCUUUCCUGUGGUGGGAGUUCUAUGUGCAGAGCAGAACAGGGAGAUCUCCCUGUGAGGUAAAGCCCCCAUGAACAAUAGGGACUCUGGUCGUCAAGACAACCACUAAAUUACUGCCUUCUUCCCUCUUUUGUGUCUUGCCUUUCUUCCUGGUGCUUCAGCACUAAGGGUUUUGCUCCCUCUCCCUGCCCUUUCCCCUCCACGGACUCAAUUUUCUUCUGAAUGGGUGGCCAUUUUAAUUACCUUCCCCCUUCCCCACCCCACCUCUCUGCCCUUGCCCUUGCUGCUGAGAAAGGCAGGCUCAGGAUAACUACCUGGGGACUGAGAAUGAGCCAGGCUUGCUGUUCACACGGGGACAAGGAAAGAAGAGACAGAGACAUUUGGAUCCUAUAGUCUCUGCAGUGAAAGUUUUAUUGGUUGGUACAUGGAGGUCUGGUUUUAGGAAGGAUUCGGAAAUAGAGUUUUCAUAUUAUCCAAAACCCCCUGAGGCCUCGUCCCAAUUUUCUUAACUGCUCAGUACCAAAUGCUUUACUGGUUUCAGUAUUUACUUCCCUGAGCCUGCCAGGAAGAGUAAGCUUUACAAGUGAGAAAACUGAGGCAUGAAAUGCAAAGCUUACUCCAGAUCCUGCCAUCAUUAGUUCGCUGAACCUGGUUGAAUUUUUACAGAAGGUCUGAAGUAGUCUUUUUCUCUUUUACAUGUGCAAACACACAAGCACUUUUAGAAAUACUUUUUAUUUUUCUUAUUUCAUCUUGAUGAUAACUUUGUGAAAAAGGCAAGGCAAGAAUUUGCCCAUUUUAUAAUGAAGGAAGCCAGAGCUCAGAGAGUUUGUUCAACUUUUAUGUGGUUAAGCCAGGUUCAAACCUGUCUGUCGCUUUUCAGUGUCAUUUUUAAAGUCUGUCAGUCCUGAUUUUCUCAGAACUGGAUUAUAGUAUGUCGGUAGCAACAUAGUAUGGGGCCAAAAAAAGGUUGACUUGAAAGACUUCAGAGGCACACUAGAUUUGUGCAUAGAAAACUUUCAGAUUGGCCGGGCGCAGUGGCUCAUGCCUGUAAUCCCAGCACUUUGGGAGGCCAAGGUGGGUGGAUCAUUUGAGGUCAGGAGUUUCAGACCAGCCUGAUCAACAUGGUGAAACCCCGUCUUUACUGAAAAUACAAAAAAAAUUUGCCGGGCAUCGUGGCGCAUGCCCUUAGUCCCAGGUACUCGGGAGGCUGAGGCAAGAGAAUCACUUGAACCCAGGAGGUGGAGGUUUCAGUGAGCCGAGAUUGCACCACUGCACUCCAGCCUGGGCGACAGAAUGAGACUGUCUCAAAAAAAAAAAAAAGAAAAAACUUUCAGAAUGAAAUCUUAAACAUGUCACAAUACUCAAAUAUAGAAAUUGUUAGAGCUUUCCCUUUACAAUCAGUCUUAUUUAUCCUAAAAAUACACAGACCCCAAGUGUCUUUUUCUCUUUCUACAUUUGUUAGAAAGGUAACCUGACCUUUGCUUUUGGUCUUUCCUCCCCCAUUCUGCUACCUUCCUCUCUUCUUUUCUUCUUACUAGUUUCAAAUAAUGGGUUGGAAUCAAUUCAAUGCUGCUCCAUCCGUCAGAGGCACUUCCCAAAAUACAAGUGUGACUCAUAGUCCUCAUAACCCCCCUUUGCUUUUUGUUUGACUUUCAAUCUCUUCUAUCCUCUGGGCCUAUUUCCCAGGAAAAUUGACCAAACAUAAGCUACUGGCAGCUGUCUCUCUCCUCCAGGAUUUAUAGUGUGAGAUAAGGAGCAUGGCUGACCCACUCCCUUGCCUUCCAGCUCUCUUCCCUUCCAGAGGAAUGCAUAGCCAGGUGUGAAUGCCCAUUUCAUGGAUUAUUCUUAGUUCUAGACCACCUGACUUAUUACCUAGCAUACCCGUUACAACAUCAGCUCUAUCGCUGGUGUAUUAGCCCACAGUUUCAUUUUAUUAUUAGCCUAAACAAAAGAUUAUUAGGAAAGUAAAUCUGUCAGACGUGUAUAUAAACAUAUAUGGAAUGCCAAAUAUAAAGGAUUUUUAUAUUGUCCAUGAUUUUUUAAAAUCUAUAAUUGUCUUCCUCUGUAAGCAUGAAUAAUUAAGAGCUCAAUGUUUUUGCUGUUGUAAGUAUUGGGAUGUAUGCUUUCUGCAGAACCUAUUUUGAACUGUGUGCCAUGCUUUAAGACCAGUGUUUGUCCCAUAUACAGCAUGAAUUCACUUAGUAACCAAUAUUUAUUGAUUGCUUUCUCUGUGGUAGGCACUUCGUUAAGUGAUCAAAAUACAAAAAAAAAAAAAAGACCCAAAUCCCUACCAUAGGAAGUGUGAUAUCCAAUUGGAGGUGCAAACUUAUAAAUAGGAGUUGUAGUAUAAAAUCAGUGCUUUGAAAAGAACUCUAUAUGUGAUUCAGAGAAGGGAUUUAUCAAUUAUGAGAGGUGCAGGGAAGGCUUAUAGUAGAUGACAUCAGAGAUGAGAUUUAAAGAAUGUGGGGCGUUGCCAGCGGACAGUGAGAGAGAGAGAGAACAUUCAAGGCAGAGCAGUAAAACAAUAUAGUGUAUUUGUGGUACUCAAAGAAGUUAGUAUGAUUGAUUAGGAAUAUAUGAUAUGCAAGAAUAAUGGCUGAUGAUAACAGUGAAGAGUUUAAAGGGAGUCUGCUCAUUCAGACUCCUGUGAGUCAUUCCAAGAACAAAACAUUUGUCACUCAUUUGAUAGGAAACAAUUUUACAAAACAUAAACAGAUGAUGACAUGAGCAAAUUUGCAAUUGAGAAAAAUCAUUUAAAUAGUGCUGUGGAGGAUUAAUUAAUUGAAGGGGCCAAAGUUAGAAACAGGAAGACAAAUUAGGGAGGAGUUUCAUUGAUAGAAAAGGUGAUGAGGCAUUCAGCUGAGAUCAUUGCUAUAGAGAUGGUAAAGGGGUAAUAGAUUCAUGAGAUAUUGAGGAGGUAGGAUCACCUAUAUUUAGUGACUAUUUAAAUGAUUAUGUGGUGUUGGAUUAGGGUUGAGAAAAAGACAAAUCAAGAAUGACUCACACAGUUUUCCACCUUGCAGAUUGAGAAGCAUAACUAAAAAGAUGGGGUAAUAUCUUUCUGAACAGCAUAUUGGGGUUGUGGUUAAAAUCCUGUUGCUUACUAAAGUAAUAGAUUAGUAUCUACUCUGAUUUAUAUAAAAAUCAAUGAUGCACCCAGAGAAGCCUGUACUGUAUCUCUAAUAAUUUUGAGAUUCUUUUUAGUAGAAAACUUAAGGCCCAGAUUAUAUUUUCAACUUUUUUUCUAUCUGUAAGUUUCUUUAGAAGAAAAAUGAAAACAGAGAAUGAAUAGCUAACCUUGUAGCUGGUACCAAGGCAAGGUUUUUAAAUUUUCUGUGCCAUGACGUAUGAUUAUUCACAUGGUGAACUUCUGACCACAGACAGAAUACAACUCAAAAAUAGUAGAAAGAAUGUGUUUGUCAGCAGACCAUCAACCCAGUGAAGAGUAAGACAUUGACAAAAAAAUUCAGAUAAAGUUAAAACUGGAUAUUGAGAAAAACAGCUGACACAGAAAGGAAAGCAGAGAUAGAUGAGAGUACUGGAAUUCACAGGAGCGUAACAGAAUGAGAUAAAAACUGUUUUACAUGCUGUAAGAACAGAUUAACUUAAAAUUCACGCCUGAAGGUAUCACUCAAAGUUUUGCAACAGGAUCGAUUCAUUCAGUAAAUAUUUGAUUGUUUAUUUGUGAAUGACACUAUUAAAUGCUAAAGGAGAUGUCAAAAUGAAUUACAUAAGAUUUCUGCCUUCAAAACCUUAAGAGUCUUUUUCUGGGGGGUCGGGGGGCAUUUACAAGAAGCUCAACCAAUGCUUUGAGUAAAUGAAUGAACAAAUUAAACACCCAUUUCCAAUGAGGAAGAAAAAGAGUCAGCAUCAAAUGAAACCAGGGUAGUUAACUGCGAUCAGAUUCUAGGUGAACAUAUUUUAAAAACAGAAAGAGGGGACACAUACUGAACAAUGCAAAAAUAGUAGUAAUAGAACUAGUAAGAACAGGGUCCAGUAAGCUUCAACUCAGAAGGAGCUGAGGUUGUAGAUAAAUAUUAAGGGAAAAGACUUAGGUGAAAAACACAUACACGUGUCACAUGUUACUAACAAGAAAAAAUAUAUGUAGGUAAUUGUUUGGGACAGAUGCUGUAGUAUCAACUGAUUACAUGGUGAAAGCAUUUAUUCAUUCAUUCAGCAGUGAAUGAAUGGGUCUAUUAUUUGCUAGGCUGUUUUCUAUUUUCUUUGUCAAGGAAAAUGGCCUAGCAAGAAGAAUUGAACAGACAUGAUUAAAGUAGAAUUGGCGACCAAAAUAGAAAUGAAAAUAAUAAUAGAGCACGUAACCUAUUUUAAAGUUUGUACAUUUAAACCUGUACAUGGCCUAGAUGAAUUAUAUCCCAUGAAACUUAACAAAUUUAUAUUUAACAUUAAAGACCUAAGGUCAUUAAGAAACAUUGCCAUUUGUCCAUAUGGGUUAGAGAUGCACAGAUAUCUUGCCUUUUUAAAAAAUGGUUAAAGGUUCUUGACCCCAACAUUUAUUUCUGGAAAUUUCUGAAGCAGAUGACGAAAUAGAUGUUUGUGAACAUUUGGGAAGGGCAAUGGGGAACCCUAGAAACCAUUAUGGGUUCAGUAGGAGUGUGCCCUGCCUGAUUAGCAUGCAGUUGUAGUUACAUUGUGUAUGGAUUCCAACAAGUUUUUGCCAUAAUAUCCAUAUGGACAGAAUGGAAUAUGUUGCCUGCAUUAUAGUACAUUUAAGUAAUUUGUGGCUAGUCGAGUGUCUUUAGCCCAAGGGUAUUAAAUAAUAUCAUAAACUGAUGCCAUCCUAGAGGGAAAUUUCUAGUAAUAGAGCACUGCUCUUCAUCUUAUCCUGAUCAAUUUUUUCAUCAGAAAAUUUGCAAGUAAUUCUAAUCUUAGAGGAGUAGUUAAAACUCUAGAUGAUGAAAAUUAAGAUUCAAAAACAUUUAGAAAACUUAGAAUGAUAAUCUAAAGCCAACAAGAUGAACUAUAAUUUAGAUUUUUUUUUAAUUGCACAAAUACAGAAGGGCAAGACUAUACUUAACAGAGGGGCACACGAUUUUUUUUUUUUUUGUAAUGUACCUGUGUGGACUUAGGAUUUUAGCUGGCUGAAAACUCAAUAUGAGUCAGUGCUUUUGACGUGUGUGCCAAAAAGCUAACACAAUCUUCGGCUGUAUGAGAAGUAUAGUAUCUAAAUCUAAAGGAAGGCUCAAUCCCCUAUGUUCUUUGCUGGUCAGGUCACAUCUCAGAGCUGUUUGGUUCUGGGCACAUCAUUUUAAAAGAAAAGCUAAGCAGCACACCCAGAGGAUGGAGCCAGGUUGAGGAGUGGUUCAUUUCUCUCCUUCUUUCAUCAGACAUUUAUUGAGUGUCUUUGAGGUUGGCAAAAUCACGGAUGUAUGGGAUGUAGAAGAGACAUAGGGGAGAAAUAAUAGCUGAAUUUAAAAAUGCAAAAUGUUGUCUUUUGGAAGAGAUUUAACCUAAUAUCUGGUAACUCCAGAGAGUAGAACUAGGACCAAUGACUAGAAUUCAUUAACACAAGGAGGCCGAUUUGGGUUGGCAAGGUUUAAGAAGCAUCUUCAAUGAAUUUAGAUUAUGCUUUUAAGGAAUUAAGCCACUUGCCUGAGGUCACAUUGCUAAUUGGGUAGCAGAACUAAGAUAAAAGCCCAAGUUUCUGGAUUCACAGGACCCAACCCUUGUCUAUGCCGUUAUAUUACAGAGGAGGUUUCUGCUUUGGGAGGAGACUGGAUAAAAUAACCUCUAAGUUUCCUUCCAACUCUCAAGUUGUAUGUUCUUAUAAGCCACUUGAUGUAAAAUAUUUCCUUUUGGUGCCCAAUGCUUUCAUAUGUAGAGUUGGUGAGAUUGGAAAAACCACUAAGGUUGAACAGAUGAUUUUUUGAAGUUCCUUCCUUAAGAAUCCUUCCAUUUUUUAAUACAUAUUAAUUUUAUAUCUGUGAUGUGUACAUUACUAAUCAAAAACAAAAACUGUUUGUGGCUAGAUAUAAAUGUAUGGAACUCAGAUUCUUAUAUUGUGGUAUUUAGGAGAAUGUCAAGUCUUCCCUUGAAGUACAUGAUUCAAAGAUGUGGAUCCAUGAUUUAAAACAUGAAAGCAAAAAUCAGAGAAGAAAUUGUGCCAACUCUGAGCCAUUUUAGAUUUCACAGUAGUAUUGGGAGAAAGAAGUGGUAGUUUCUUGCCCUCGGGGUUCAUUUCCUCCUCAUUCUUCCCCAGCACUGGGCAGGAAAGGAUGGUGACCUAGAUACACAGUCAGAGGGCAGCAGUGUUGAACUUUCUCAGACACAGCUGAGUAACUUGGGUCUGGAUAGUUACAGGACAGAAGCCUAGAGCUGAGAGCUGACAGGGGAAACUGUCUAUAAACACAAGAAGGGGCCAUGGCAGGAAGACAGAGGCCUGGGAACGGCAUCAGAGAGAAAAGAAGUAUAACUUUUAUCAGGUGUGAAAUGGGCAAAAACAUUUUGUUUAAUGGAUAAUGUCCUGAAUCUACACCAUCACCUCCAAGACCUCCUUUCUCUCCCACCCUAUAGAUUGCUGCUACUGAUUGGAUGAGCCAAUACUCAUACUUAUGUGCUAGGACUGGCAGUACAGAACACAGUGUUCAUGGUUGAGGCCCCUGCAAACAUUUUACAGGGUGCUUGGGUGGGUGGAGAUGGGGAGCAUUUCCAGGAAGCUAAAAAUGUGGCUUGGGCUUCUCCUACUUUCUCUCGGAACUCCUAAUUCUUGACACUGCAUGAGUGUUUUUCAAACUUUUUUUAAAACUUCAACCUACAGUAAAAAAUGCAUUGUACGUUGCAGCCCACUGUGAGCAUGCACAUAGGCACAGGCGCAUACACACAUAUGCAUGCACGCAGAUCUGAUAUAUACAUAUAUAUGUACAUACAUACGAAACAAGUGUCUCCAAACAUGAGAUGCCUUUUUAUGUUAUCACAAACAACAAAACAGAUGAUAUGACCUCUAAUGAUGUCCAGCCCACAGGUCGAAAAACAUUGCGCUACAACCAUGAGGUUUAAAAUGACUGUGAAAGUAGCCUGAUACAAUUAUAUCCAAAAGUCCCUGGGUCUAAGGCAGUAAUUCUCAACUGGAGCAAUUUUGUCCUCAGGGGACAUGCCGCAAUGUUUGGAGACAUGUUUGGUUGGCAAAACUAGCAUCUAGUUUGAGGGGAGGAGGGGCAAGGAUGUUGUGGAAUGUUUUAUAAUGCACAGGAAAGCCCCUAUGACAAAGAUUUCGCAGUCCAAAAUAUCAGUAGUACCAACGUUGAAAACCCUGCUCUCAGGGUAAUAAAAUAAGUCAAUACUUCUAAUUUACUGAAGGUGUACUUAGGAUGAUAGAAGCUUUAACUUGAUCUUCCUUUUCUUUCUCUUUUCCUUUGAACUGUAUUUGGUAUCUUAAGGUUGGAGCAUAAUUGCCCUUGGAUUGUCUAUAGAGGUACAGCCAAUAGAUAAAUAGGCUGGAAGGAAUGGACCUGUUAUUUUCCUUAUAUUUAGACUGCACCAGGCAUUUUUGUUUAGAAUAUUGUUGUGGAUCUUAUGAAUAUUUUCUGUUUUAUGAUUUUAGUAUCUUCUUCCCUUUCUCCUCUUCAUUAAGCCAUACUGAUUCAAGACCCUUUCUCACUCAGCCAUAGCUGCUGUCUUAGAAAAGAAAUGAAGGGGAUUUGGCUAAUUGGAUUAGACAUGGUCUCUAAAGCCUUCUCCUUACUCAUGAGAUUUGAUUCUGCUGUUUUGAUGGGAAAUGACCUUCUACUAACCUUGAAGUGCCAUCUUAAGCCCUAGUAUUAAACUGUCUCCUUUUUAGUCAUUGCUUCAUUCCCCUAUCUGCGGCUAUUUCAGACCAGGUUCCCUUGAACAUGGAGUGGAUGUGCAGUCCCAGCUACUGACAAGCCCUGAUCUCCACAUCCUUUCUUCUCCCCUGUCUGGCAUAAGGGAAGCUCUUGAAUGUCUUGGGGUCAAAAUGUGGUUGUGGAGUGGGGUUUUUUGGCCAUUUUACUGGCUAUUUCUAGGCCCCCUAUUAAGGCUCUGAAUCAUUCAGAGAUGGCUUGACACAAGAGACCUGGUUUGGGUUCUUUUUUCUUCUCUUCUUUGGGAUGAAGGCAGGAUAAUAGAAAGAGAUAUCUCUAAAUCAAAUAUCAGACCUGGAAUAGUAGUGGAAAAUAAAACCAGUGCUAUCUGAGGCUAUUCUCUACCAUAUUUAUUUUAGCAUAUUUACUUCAUGCAUCUUGUAUUACAUGAACAAGAGCAUUUGUAUUUAGUAAAUGAUUUAUUAUAAGUAAUUUUUUUUUUUUUUUUUUUUUUGAGAUGGAGUCUCCCUCUGUCACCCAGGCUGGAGUACAGUGGCGUGAUCUUGGCUCACUGCAGCCUCUGCCUCCUGGGUUCAAGCGAGUCUCCUGCCUCAGCCUCCCCGAGUAGCUGGAGACUACAGGCGUGCGCCACCGUGCCCAGCUAAUUUUUUUUGUAUUUUUAGUAGAGACGAGGCUUCACCAUGUUGGCCAGGCUGGUCUAAACUCUUGACCUCAGGUGAUCUGCCCGCCUCAGCCUUCCAAAGUGCUGGGAUUACAGGUGUGAGCCACUAUGCCCGGCCUAUUAUAAGUAAUUUCUAAUGAAUAGUAAGAGAAACGUGUGUGUGUGUUGACCUUGAAGCUUUAGAUUUCUGUCAGCCUAAUAGUAAAUGGUACCAGCAAAGUCCAGAAACUGAUGCUGGAAAACCUCCUAUGAUGUAUUAGAGUUCAGACACAUAAAUUCCAUCCCUUCCACUUAAAGAGAGCUCUAUAGGGUUACGAAUCUCUUUUUAACCUUCCCACUCCUAUGAUAAGAAUAGAAAGAUGCAGUGUAGAAAUCGCGAGAUGAAGAGAGUUAAUGGAGAGGAGUUGAGACUUCUGCCCCUUUUAACAAUCCUACACCUAAUGUCUUUGUCUUCCGUGCUCUAGCCAGUUUCCAAAUAAAUCAAGCAUGAUUAGGGGAGUUAAUAAAGUUAGAUAAUGAAAUGGUGGUGUGUAUGGAGCUUUACCUUAGAGAAGGAUGAUAGAACCAAAGGAAGGGAAGGUAGGGAUGAAAGGGAGAGGAAAGAUAUUUGGAUGAAGAAAUCUCCACCUUCUUCAUUGCUCUCAAGAACCAGUGGCAGUUGGUUCCAUCCAGGUGUUGGGCAAGGCAAAGUAUACCAAAUCCCUGAAUAUACAGCCAUUUACAACUUAAGAAAGGCAUAGUGAGUGAUAAUAAAGUGUGUCUUAGAAAUUGAAUUACAGCUUAAAAAAUUUAGAGAUUGUAUUGUGUGAGGGCAGUGGCAGUUGUGGUGGUGAUUUUUUUGGUUUGCUCUUUAUCAUGUUUUCCUUCCAGAUUGGCGUGCUCAUCAUUUUUAACGAGACACCAUCGCUCAGAAGUUCUGUGAACAAGAAAGAUUUGUUGCACUUGGUCUUCUACACAGGCUGCCUGGGACUAGGAAAUAAGACCAUGCUGAGCCCAAAGGCCUAGGAUAAAGCCUCUGUUUGCUGACAGGGGGAAGGGUGGGCAGAACGUAGGCAAGAGGAGAAUCCAGGAAAGAGAGCAAAUGUUUAAACCAUGCGUGGUGCAAGUGUGUGGUUUGUGUCUUUUAUCUUCAGAGUGUGGAGAAGAAUAAGGAAAGCUGGCACUCUGCAGCUCCCAGGGACUAGAAGUCACUUUCCAAACUCUGUCCCUCUUUGUAGGCCUGGAGGGAGUUUAUUUCUGCCAGUUUGUGAAAGUCCUGUUUCUUAUAUUCCUGGGCCUGACUUUUUCCAGGGCCUCCUGUUGGCCAGUUCUGUGCCUUGUAUGUACAGUGCUUGACAGUGUCUUUGUCUCAUCAGCAGCUGAUACUUACUCAGAGAUGGCACUCCUUUUCUUCGGUGAGUUGUGCUUAUUAGCUUCCACAAAUUUAUUUGACUCAUAGACUCAUCUUCAUCAUCAGGUGCUUAUUUUUACUUUUCCUACUUUUAUGUCUCUCCCCAACAUUUCCAUUUAGAGUCUGAAAAGCUGUCUUAUAGAUUUGUAUAAGUUUAUAAAUUUAUAUUUUGCCACAUGAUAAAAUUCAUUUUGCAUCCCACACAUGUACAUGAGACACUUAAUCACCAUGCAAGAGAACAAGGAGGAUAUCCUUGUCCUAAUGCCAUGUGAGGUCCUGUCCCCAUCAGAUAAAUUAAUGUUCAUUCAAAAGAAUGUAACUCUUGCUUUGUAAGACAUGCCAGAAGAUGGCUGAGGUACCUAGGCUUGCUGGCAUGUUACAACAUGUUCAGUCUAGGAAGGAUCAUGUGGCUAAAGAUUUUAGUUUGCAAGACUUUGCCCCUCUCCCUCAAGACAGUUAGAUGAGACCCUAAGACACAUCAUUCUCCUCAGCAAAAAUUGCAGAAGUAUACAUGGCUUGAGGUGAAGAAAGGAGACCUUGGGUCACUUAAUCCCCUGCAGAGAAGCCGAUCAGGUCAUUGCAGCCACCUCCCUCUAGUGACCCUCUUACAUAAACAGGAACAGGAAUUCUUGCUACUGGAUUCCUUUCAUCAGGCAUCUUAGGCUCACUGAAUGAAAAGCCCUAUAAAAAGGAGAUGCGGCCCUAAUAAUAACAAAUACGAUCGUGUUGGCUAUUUUGGACAAGAACAGCUUUGUGCCACUCUUGAUCUCCAUCGAUGGCUGCCAUUCUUGCCCUGCUAUUACCUUACACACUUCCUAUUCUUAGAAUCAGUUGUGAGCCUUGGGCUUGGGGGAUUGCAGCCCUCAUGGCUGGAAUGCCCAGCUUGAGUGGAAUGCAGACUGUCUGGCAGAGUGGAGGUUAAAUAAAGUUUGCCUUGGCAGCCCCCUCUGCUCUUGGAUGAGUGACAAGUGACUCGAGUAUAGGAGCGAGGAGUGAUGGCAUGAGCUGCCAUGUGGUGCAGGAUCAAACGAGUCUUCCGUGCAUGAAUAGAAGUGGUUGAUUGUCCAUCCAUGACCCACACAGCUAUGUCAGUCUUAAAUGAGGUGGGUGAAGGGGAGGCCUCAACAGCCUUGAACCUCACUUCUGACCAUAUCACUUUGAAAAAAAUUCAGGAACAGAUCAAGAAUAACGUUGAACCACUUUCUAGGUUUCCAGCUGAACUCCAGAUUUGGUAUAUCUUCCCCCUCAUUUUUGACUCAUUUUUGAAAGUAAGAUAAAGGGAAAAUUUUGACUCAUUUUCGAAAGUAAGACAAAGGGAAAAUUUUUCAUUGAAAUAAGAACAGUUAUCAGUCAGUCAACCAUUUCUUGAGCACCAAGCACGGCGGGGAGUUUUUUUAAAGUACAAGACACAGAACUCUUACAGCUUAUAAUUUAGUUGAAGAAGUAAAGCUAUAAACACCUUUAAAAAGAUGCAUAUUCCAAAGUAAUUGUUCCAGAGCUACCUGCCAAAGGAGGUCUAUGGAGAAGGAGAGCACUUCCAGCUGUGAUGGUCAAGGAUUUCAUGGAGGAAGUAGGGUUGAAACAGGUCUUGCCAGAAGGGCAGACUUGAGACUUGCUCUUCAGGCAAGGCGAGAAGAGGCCCUUGUUAGUGAGAGAACUAUUAUGAACAAAGGGCAGAUGUAGGAAAUCCCUAAGACAGUCAUGAGGACCAGAAGAUAUGGCUGGGGAGGUAGAGAGAGGAAUUUGUUUAAAGAUCGCUAAGUCCGUAGCUGUGAAGUCUGUGUGUACAUGUUACCAAGAAGGUUAUAAUGCUUCCCAUCAGAGGAGAGCUAGAAAGAUAAUAGGUGCAGCCUUGCCAGAGGAGAGUUGGGAAGGUAUAGGUGCAGGCUCACCCAGAGACGGAGGCCCUUUUAGUGUUCUGUUCUGUAAAACUUCUUGUACGGUAGAUGGCACAUAGUGAACGCUCCAUAAAUAACACGAUUCUUAUUGUUACUCAUCUUCAAAUUCUGUUAUCCCAGGCUGUUGAAUUGUCUUGGUUUCCUUUGCAAGAGUCAGUGCUGACUUUGUCCUGUUCUGAUUGCUCAUGUAAUUCAUGGUAUCUUAGUCUGUUUGGGCUGCUAUAACAAAAUACCAUAAACUGAAUGGCUUAUAAACAACAGAAAUUUAUUUCUCACAGUUUCUAAAGGCCGGGAGGUUCAAGAUCAAGGUACCAGCAGAACUGGUGUCUGGCAAGGGCCCUUUUCCUUGUUCAUAGACAGCUGUCUUCUCCCUGUGUCCUCAUAUGGCAAAAGGGGUGAGAAGUCUCUCUCAGGUUUCUUUUAUAAGGGCAUUUACCUUUGCCCCCAUGACCUAAUCACCUCCCCAAAGGCCCCACCUCCUACUGCCAUCACCUUGAGGGUUAGGAUUUUGACACACGAAUCUGCAGGGGAACAUAAACAGUCAGUCCGCUGCCUUGUUAUUUCCUUUCCUUCAGCUUUAUCUAAGCUUUCGUCUCUCUUCUACCACAGGUGGCUAGAGGUGCAGGUAGCUAAUUUAACAAGUCCACAGCGCUGGGUGCAGUACCUCCUGCUUCUUCAGGAGUCCAUCUGGCCUGGUGGAGUUUUGCCUAAGUUUCCACGGCCCGUAAGGACCCAAGAGCAGAAACUGGCUGCUGAGAAACAGGCUUUGCAGAGCCUGAUGGGAGUCCUCCCAGGUAAUUGGACCAAUGAGAUCAAUUAUACCAAUCACAUUUCUCUUCCAUUCUGCUUUGCCACCAUUACCCCUGCACCUUUUCCUGUUUGUAAAAGGGCCCUGAAUGUGGCUAGAUUCAAAACUCUGUUGACCCAUCAUUUCCCAGGCUAAUAGGAAAAUGAACAGGGCUGCAAUUCUUUUAUCCAUUGCUCAGCUGAUGCCAAGGGAAUGGAAAGGAACUCUACAGCUGCACCCUAAAUACUAGGUGACAAUCCUGCAGAUAUUUAGGUUAAUAACUUUCUCUCUACCUGCUGGCAGGUCUGGGGAAGCUCUGCCUGCAGGGACAGGUCUCAGAGCCAUUUCCAGGAGAUGAAGACUUCAGAUUCUCUACCAAUUCAUAGCAUUUUGGGACCAAGGAAGAAAAUCACAUGUCUCACAGAAGCUCCAACUUAAUAAAUUGCAGCCAUUGAGUAUGGUACAUGGCCUUUAGCAAUAAGUUAAAACAAAAUCUGAGAAGGUUGUUUUUCCUUGCAUUGUGUUUUUAGAGGGCCAGGAAGGCAGUUUGUUGCCUAUGGCUGUGAUAACCAGGAAACAAUUGUGAACUUAGCUCUGGACAAUCAGUUUUAUUUACCCUUAUUAUUAUAACUCUGUUUGCCAACCUAAACUGUUACAUUGGAAGGAGUACCUGCAUUUGAGUGACAGGUUACAAAAUAAUUUUUGAAGCCCAUUCUUAUGUAGACACCUAACUUGAGAAACAUAUUUUUCUCAGGUUUUUCCUGUUUUGUGAGGAUUUUAGUUUGGCUGUAUGGUUUAGAGGUAGGCCUGAAAUACCUAACCUAUGUAAAAACGGCAGAGAUCCUGGGGAGAGACUGUCCUUAGAAUCUAAAACUUCAGUGAUAACACGCAAAUUCCAUCUGUUUUUUCCUCCUCAGAUCUCGUAGUAGAAAUUCUUGGGGUGAACAAAUGCCGGCUGAGCUGGGGUCUAGUCCUGGAGUCACUACAACAACCCCUCAUCAACAGGUAAGUGGGAAAAUGUUAUUCCAACAUCAGCAUAGUUACAGCCACCUCUGGUCUCAGAGGUAUCCAAGGUUUCUGAGUGAAAAGCCCACAUUCCAAAGAAUAGGAUUGUAGUCUUUACUUGCUCUGGGCACUGACUACAGAGUUUGACGUCCAGAUCCACACACUCUAAGUAAAAUCCACACCAUCAGGCUUCUGAGCAGGUCGUCAUGUGCUAGGAAAUCACUCUUGGACCACCCACCAUUUGUGUUUGGAAGAACUCUAUGCAGGCCCCCACAUGAGCUGCUGAAAAUGACCUCUUAUCCUCCAGGCUUGUUCAGCAUACUUGCUCAGUGCUCUUUCCAACAUCUGCCAGCCCCUGUGAAUGCUCCAAGAGCGUACCCUGGCCUGUGUAUCACAGACCAUGUAAAGAUGUUCACCAUGAGCCCUGGCCUUAUAGCAAAGCUGUGAUUCAUGUCAAGACCAGGAGUUGUCUUUGCUUCAUAUCAGGUAGACAAGAUAGUAAGGUUGGAAUUUCAUAAAGGGACCAGAAAUGCUGGGUGAAGAGUCCUAGAAUAAUCCAGAAGAGGUAGAUUCCAUCCCUUGGGCUGUUACUCUUCUGGAAGUAUUGAGUAACCUUGCACUCAAACCCUACCCCAAAGUAGACUGUGUUCGUUAACUUCCUCAAGGAUCCUGGCUUUACCUCACUGCCUGUAAGGCAGCCUAUAAAUUUAAGGUAAUUAAUUAUGAGAAACAGCAGUAGUCAGGAGCUCUGAAAGUGUCUAGUAACCUGACAUCUCAAGGAUUUGUUAUCACAGUUCUUCAGAGCAGUGCUAAUGUAACUAUGUAAAGAGAAAUGGAAUUUUAUAAAACUUAGUCUUAUAUAAAACUAGUCUUAUAUAAAAACUGUUCUUGCCUUUAUUAGGGUCAGAGGCUUUAUUAGUUCAAAAAACAUUAAUUUCAUGGCAGAGGUUUCAUCAAGCUAUUGAAGUUUAGGGUGUCGGUGAUGGGGGAGGAGAAAAUAAAUGUCAUAAACAGGAUCUUGUGUUUCCUGAUUGAGCCAGACCCUAAGUUUUUUGUCCAUUCGUUUCAGGCAUUUGAUUUACUGCCUUGGGGACAUCAUCCUGGAAUUCUUGGAUCUCAGUGCCUCUGUUGAGGAGUCUGCUGCUACCACCUCUGCCUCAGAUACCCCAGGCAACUCUAAGAGGAUGGGUGUCUCCUCUUAGCUGGUUAUUCACGCCUUCUUCCCAGGUCAGGGAAGUAGAGUUACUCGGCCACCAGAGACCAGUCAGGAAGCCCGUGCCCUCUUCAAGUAGGCUACAGCUAAGAAGGCCUAGGUUCUCGGUGGCUCACUUCUCUCCCACUUCUGCUCCAUUUGUAGCAGGUGACAGGGGUCUGUGUGUCCCAGUUGUAUGCACGUUUAUUUCCCUGUUCCUUUUGUGAUGUUGGGAUUGUUGCUGGUGAGUAGAUCCUGUUUCCUUUGGGAAAAGAAGCUGUGAGGUAGAGGAAUGAACCCCUUUUGCUUCUCCUUUUGCCAUCCUCCCUGAGAUUGUUUGCCAGAAUCCUGGCCCUGUGCACACAUGUGCUUAAUCCACCAGCACACAAGCUCUAGAUAGAACAGGAAAAAAACUGUGGCCAGAUUUCCUUGGAGGAGAAAACAACCUUCUCAGCUCUCUGUUCCUACCCGGAAACUAAAAAUUCAUUCAGGGCCAUUCUCAAAAACCAGACUCCUGGGUCUAAUCUAGUUUCCCAACAGUUCCAGAAGAAGAAGGAGGGAAGAAAAUUUUUCAAGGAACUUCUUGCUCAUGUGUUGCUGUUUCCCAACACAUCAGCCUUAUGGAAGAUGUCAUGAGGCUGCUUGCCUGGGAGGCUACACUUUCCUUUCCAGAAGACUUCAAAGCUGACUGCCAAAGCUUCUGGUAAAUCCACCCCACCCUUCACACCCUUUCCUGAAAGGCAUUUAUACCACCCAUUUUAUUUAUUGGCUUUGCUCCCAACCCCCUGCCCUAGAGCAAUUGAGUUUUUGAAUUUUUGACCCUCUCUCUGUCUUCAGCAAAACUGCAUGACAAGCUGCAUAUUCAGCCUCAGUUUUUCCAAGGAGAAUGGAAAGCACUUGCCUCCUGUCUUAAGAAUGCACAAAGAGUAGGACUAGCAAGGCUGGGGGAUGAAAUCUCCCUUCCUAAGUCUUUGACAGAGAACUUUUAUUAUUCUGAACAGAUAAGAUUAGCAAACUUACAAGGAAUAGCUUCUUAUUUCCCAUUCCUUACGGUUAUAAUCAGUCCUUUAACAACACCAGCAUGAAGGCAAAGGUGUUUUGUCAGACUGCAACAUCUAUUAGAAAGGCAAGGCAACUGGGAAUUGCUGGAGAAGGAUAAAUCAGGAGGAAUUGCUGGUAGAAAAGGCUGCAGACAGUCACAGGGAAGUGCUGUAUAUUAAAUGCAUGUGAAUAGCUGGCAAAAAGAUGUCAAGGAUGUCACUGGGAGCCCUUUGGCUUCACACUCGCCUGUUAGCGCCUUGCUUUCGCUGAAUUACCAGAGCCUACCACUCGGAGGAAGGUCUUGGAGUUAGACUGAUGAGAAGGCAAUGGGGUGUCAAAAACAAGUGUCAAAGUUCUCUUAGAUUCUGAAGUCGGUGAUGAGCACACAAUUAAAGUGGUUUGUGGAAGAAAGUUGUAAAAUCUUUUUACUUUUUUGCCCCUCUGGAGGCUUUUAACCCUAAAUUGUGUCUGAUGUAUUCGGGAGGCUUAGGUGUGCAAUUCUUGCCCAAAGGCAAGGAGAUGAAUGAGAUGUCUCAUGGCCUCUUCUAGCCUUAAAAGUUGACCAUUACAGUGACUUUAUGGCUCCAAAGUUCUUGAAGCAUCUCCAGCCCUAGACUUUGACAAGAAAAGGUAGCUCAGCAUCUCUACUUUCCGUGAGUACCUGCAGGAGUCCAGCCAAUGUAUUAGAGCUGAUCAUUAAGCUCCUUCAGUGAGGGCUAAGAUCCUAUUCUCGAUGAGCAUAGGGGGACAGCCUUGUUUUAUGCCACUUUUCUCUCCCCAUACCUACCUUCCCCUCAUGUGUACUUAGCCACCUGUGUUGCUUUGAAUCUGCUGCCAGUUCUGGCUCAAAUGUGGCACAAAAUCAGUACAUCAGACACACCAUGAAAUCCCUGUGGCUAUAAAUUCUAAGGAAUCUUUUGACACUUCCAGCCCAAAGAACUUAUUUUUAUUUCGUAUUAUAUAAGAGUCCCCACCUCUACUCCACGUACCCCAAAAAGAUAAGCUGUCCUCAGAUCCUCCUUCUACCCAGGAGGGAAAUAAUGGAUAUUGCCAAGGGAACAAUCAGAACUCAUCUGGCUUUGAAAACGACCUGCCAAGUUUGGCUAGCAGGUUCAGACAACAAGAGAGUAACAAUUGGUAGAGAGCCACAGGUAGAAAAGAUACUCCCAGCUGACAGGGUGAUAAAAGGCAGGGAAGAAUUGGGCCUGUGCUGAUCCAGGAAGGUUUUAUUGUUUGCUUGUUUUUUGUAUUUACUCGUGACUAAAUUUUAUUCAUUUAAGUCAGAAUUUUGAUAUUUGAAAUAAGACUACUUUCCCUUUUCUUACUAUCUAUAAAAAAGACGAGGCAGGGAUGCUGUGUUCUUUCUGUCAAAUUCUAAAUGUGAUCUUUGCCAUUGCUUAUUUGAAUUCAAGAAAGCUAUACUUUUUCAUCACAUAUAACUCACAGUUUCAUUUUUGCAUUGUUGGAUUAGACUUAAUAAAACCUAAAUGGAAAAUAAAUUCCUAAAUCUGAGCCUAGGAGCAUGUAUAAAUUUUAUUUUUAUUAUUAUUAUACAUUAAGUUCUAGGGAACAUGUGCACAACAUGCAGGUUUGUUGCAUAUGUAUACAUGUGCCGUGUUGGUGUGCUGCACCCGUUAACUCGUCAUUUACAUUAGGUAUAUCUCCUGAUGCUAUCCCUUCCCCCUCCCCCGACCUCACAACAGGCCCCAGUGUGUGAUGUUCACCUUCCUGUGUCCAAGUGUUCUCAUUGUUCAAUUCCCACCUAUGAGUGAGAGCAUGUAUAAAUUUUAAAAUCAAUACAAGCUACUCCAAUUUCCAUUUUGGAAAUUUCCAGUUUACAAGGUGAUUUUCUUAUUGUUGUAAAGAAACACAUAAUGUGAGAUCUACCCUCUUAAGUGUACAGUACAUUAUUUAUUUAUUUUGAGACGGUACAUUAUUAACUAGAAGCAGCACAGUGCUUUGUAGCAGACUGCUACAAGUUUUUCAUCUUGCAUAACCAAAAGUUUAUACCCAUUGAACAGCCACUCCUCGUUUCCCCUCCCACCAGCCUCUGGCAAUCACUGUUCUACUUUCUGCUUCUGUGAGUUUGACUACUUUGAACGCCUCAUAUAAGUGGAAUCAUGCAGUGUUUGUCCUUUGACUGGCUUAUUUCACUUAGCAUAAUGUCCUCCAGGUUCAUCCACGUUACAGCAUGUGACAGAAUUUUCUUUUUAAGGCUGAAAACAUUCCAUUGUAUGGCUAUGCCACAUUUUCUUUGUUCAUUCAUUGAGGGACAUUUAGGUUGGCUCCGCGCCUUGAUUGUUGAAAACAAUGCUGCAGUGAACAUGGGAGUGUGACUGUUUCUUCGAGGCCCUGCUUUUAAUUAUUUUAGAUAAAUACCCAGAAGUAGGAUUGCUGGAUCAUAUAUUGUUCUGUUUUUAAUUCUUUGAAGACCUUCAUACUGUUUUCCAUAGUGACUAGACCAUUUUACAUUCCCACCAACAAUGUACAAGGGUUCCAGUUUCUCCACAUCCUCUCCAACACUUGUAAUGUUUUGUUUUUUCAUAAUGGCAUCUUAAAAGGUAUUAGGUGAUAUUACUAUCUCAUGGUUUUGAUUUGCAUAGCCUAGAACAUUUUUGAGUCUUCCUGUGUCCUACCCAGGUUAUUCAUUUCCAGCUACUGCUCUUCCUUUGCUCAUAGCACACAACACCAGUUGUUAGGUCCUGGAGGAAGUAAAAAUAUGUGUAACUAUGGUCCCUGGCUAUAUGAAUCAGGAUGCUCUGGACAAGAAUUAAAUUAUGAGGAAAAUUUAUUUUAUUUCAUAACAUUAGUACGUGAGUAGGUAAGCCCAGGAGUUUGGUGAUUCAGCAACUCUGAGACCUCUUAAGGGGCCUGAAUUCUUUCCAUCUUUCUUCCUUGCCAUUCUAAUUAGGUCAGCUGUGCUCUCAGACUGCCUGCCUUCCUGCUGCUGCAGUUUCAGGCAUCACACCCAGAGAUAACAUUCAUAAAAGAACAGGAGCAUCUCUUCUGUGUUUUCUUCUAAGGAAUGAAGGAACCAUUUCCCAGAAGUCCUUCAAGAAUCCUCUUCUAGGCCGGGCACAGCGGCUCACACCUAUAAUCUCAACACUUUGGGAGGCCAAGGUUGGGGGAUUGUUUGAGUCCAGGAGUUUAAGACCAGCCUGGAACAUAGCAAGACCCUGUCUCUACAAAAAAUAUAAAAAAUGAGCGGGGCAUGGUGGCUCUCGCCUGUGGUUCCACCUACUAGGGAGGCUGAGGCAGGAGGAUCACUUGAGCCCAGGAAUUUGAGGCUGCAGUGAGCUACGAUCACACCACUGCAUUCUAGCCUUAAGUGACAGAGUGAGACCCCAAAUAAAAAAAAAAAAAACAAAAAACCUCUUAUGACUCAUUGGCUAGAACCACCCACCUCAUGCCAAUCCACUGACACUGAGAAUGGCAUUGUGAUUGGCUUUCAAUAGUAUUUUCCCCCAGAGAUGAGGUCAUCUUCCAUGAAGGUCAGAUAUCUACAGAAAUAAUUGAUGUUAGCAAGGAAGAAGCAGAGAAUGGGUAUUGAUAGACAAUGUCUGCUCUAGGGAUGGGUCAUUCUGCCAACAUUCAGCAGAUCCCCUAUCUACUCCCAAAAUGCCUGGUACCAGCUAAUAGUUAACAUCUUCUGAGAGCAUUACUUAAAGUCUUUACAUAUCUUCACUUAUUUAACCCACAAAUCAACCCUUAAAGGUAGGUUCUGAUGUAGUGGGUUGGUGCAAAAGUAAUUGGAGUUUUGCCAUUUUAAUGCAAUUACUUUUGCACCAAUCUAAUAUAUCCCCAUUUUCUAGGUGGGGAACAUGAGGCACAGAGUGGUUAUGUCUUACCCACAGUCAUUUGCAAGGGAGUGGCAGAGCCUAGAUACAAACCAUGUCAAUCUGCCUCUGAGUCUACGUAGUAUAUCCACUAUACUAAACUGCCCUUCUACCUUACAAAGCAGAACAAGAUCAGGUUCUCACUUUUAAGGAGUCUACAGUCUAGUAUAGGAGCCAGCAAACUUUCUCUGUAAAGGUCUGGAGACUAAAUACUAGGUUUUGCAGCAGUAUGGUCUCUGUUGUAACUACUCAGCUUUUCCACUGUAGCGUAAAAACAGUUGUAGACAAUUCAUAAACAAGUGUGGCUGUGUUCCAAUAAAACUUGAUUUACAAAAAUAGGCAGCUGGCCGGGUUUGUCCCAUGAGUCAGUUUGUGGACCUGCGGUCUAGUGAGUUAGAAUACUGCUUACCAAAUUUUAAUGUGUGUGUGAUUCACGUGGGAUCGGGUUAAAAUGCAAAUUUUGAUUCAAUAGGUCCGGAGUGAGGCCUAGUAAAAGUGUAAGUGCUAUGCUCUAAAAAUGUUGACAGCAUGAUUAUCACACUCCUCUGCUGUUUGAGGGGCAGGGAGCAUUUGGAGAUGCCUUGUUUCAGGAACCCAUUCAGCCAAGUUGUCCUGGCAAGCCGUACCUCCCACAGCCCCCUCCACACCGGCUGUUUGUCCAAUCUAACUUUGCACUGGAGCAAGAUGUGUUUUCCCAGGAUGAGGAAAGGAAGGUUAGCCCACACUGCUGGAUGUGGAAGGGGAUGGGAACCAGGGAAAGAAUGGUAACUGGGGAGGAAGGGAAACCAUGAUACUUUUGUAGUCGAAGGCCUAACUGGGCGCACUCUGCCAUAACUUGGCCCCUCUGCUUCCUUUCCACUGGGAGUGCCAGAAAUCACAGGGCAGCAGUCGCUCACCCUGCCUUUGUAGACAAGAAAAUGAAACCAUCGAAGGGUGAAUUUCAGCUAGCAUAUUGCCAUCACUCUUUUAUGGUAUAAAGGAUGAGAGAGGCGGUGAGGGAGACAUUGCCCCAAACAUGAUGUCCACAUCCUAAGACUUACCUGAUAUUUCUUAUUACACAAAGACAACAUUGACUGGUUUAAGAGAGAAAAAAAAAAAGGAAAUCCAGAAGAAUGUUUUAAUUGUCAAGCGUGAAACAAGUGAAAAUCAUCAGAAUCUUUUUCCUUCUGUGACUUGGUAGCAACAGUGUGUAAAGCCAAGGCCACCGUGAAGCGGUGGGGGAAAUUUGGGCACCCGCAGACCUUGGCAGACACACUAUGCUAUUUUCAGACUUGCGGAGCCUUUGCACUGCCUCCCUGUCAUCCUCACCUGUCUCUGGUCUGAAAGUCCAUUUUAACUCUGCUUUCUUGGAGGCAGAAACAAGCAUGUGACAGGAUGCAGAGAAUUACUCCUGGCUUUGAUGUCUCUUCAACAGCUUGAUGAAACCUGGUUUUUCCACCUGUCUUCACUUCUCCAAGCCUUACCUGCAAGCGCUUCCGUGAAAGCCCCCAGCACACCAUCUCUGGGAUGUGGAAGCUUAGGAGGGGAGAAUUAAAAAAACAAAACGAAGGUAACAGUAAUCAAGAUCCAAACUUAGAAAACAUUUCUUGAAGUGACAUUAUCUGCUCCUUUUAACCCAAUCCCUUUGUCACCAGUCAGUGUUUGUUUAGGAAGUGUAAGCUAAUUUUAAUAUUAAAGUGUUGUAGUGAUUAAGAAGGUAAGUUUGUGAAUAAUGUAUGAAUCAUCCACACUUUUGUCUUUUUUCCCACCUUAUGUUCCAUGUUACUGCUGCACCCUGUUAUAAGCAAAGAAGAGUUGGCUGUGAUUACUUCCAGAAACUUUGAUUAACCCAUGAGAGUAAAGAUGUAGCUAGAUAAACACAGAACUCCCUGAUUGCAGACAAAAGGACUCAAAUGUCGACAGAAGCAAUGGCUUGUUUAUACUGUGUUGAACUGGAUUUGGUGACUUGUGAGCAUAGGUAAUCAGCCCUUUUGCCCGUGCCCCUGGGUGAAGAAUCAUCCUGCUCCUGUAACUAUCAAAAAGAUUAACCAUGAACGUUGAUAUGAAAUACUGCUUUUCAUACCUUGACACCAAGAAGAAUAGACCUUAUUAAGGGAGGAAAAACACUUUUGGAGUUUACCUCCUUUACACAUCCUGCUUGCAUGGAAUCCAAAUUCAGUGAGCUGACGGCAGGCCAGUUCCUUGCCACUUUAUGCAGUUGUGUUUAAAGUUUACCCUCUGUUAUCUAUAAAUGCAAGUGGCUUUUUCAAGAAUAGUGAGGGCAGCUUUCAUUAAGGACUCAUGCAUCUCUAGGAGAAUCACAUGGGCUUAGUUGGCAGUAGAGCAUUUUCUUGGGGACAGAAUGUAUUAUAGAUGGUUUAGGCAGGAGGUUAGACGAGAAACUUCCAAAAAAAUCUAGGGAUUUUUUAUUCUGCCCAAACCAGCAUGUUCCUUCCUGCUUUCAUUUUUUUGUUCAUGUCCUUCCUUCCACGUGGUAGAUUACCUUCUCUUCUCCAGCUGGGCAAGUAGGCUACCUCUGCCCAUAAGGACCAAUUCAAGUUCCAUUUUCAAGAAGCACUGUCUGAUUGCACCAGCCAAAACUCUUCCCACUUUCUUUUCAGUUAUUUACACUGCCUCUCUAGUCAAUGUGCAUGUAUAUGAAGUCCUCAGUAAGAGACUAUAAUUCUUCAAGGGCAACGAACAUAUCUUUUAUCUUUUUUAGUCCUAUUAUGUCCUUAUGCCCCCCCCCCAACUAUAUGUAUAUACCUAGUGCAUGAUAGGUACAAAAUAAAUAUUAAAGUUUACUUAAUUAAAGAUUAUGUUUAUUUAAGAGGCAAAAUUUGUGAAUAAGUCUGGAUCUUGAUACUGUUACUUUCAUUUUGUUGAUUCCUUUCUCCCAACCUUCCACAUCCCAGAGACAGGGUGCUGGUGACUUUUAUGGAAAGGCUUGAAGGGUGAAGAUAUGUGGAGAAACCACCGUAAACCUCUUUGAGAUUAACCACUUAUUCCAGUGGAGGGCACUGGCUAGUCUGUACCAGACCUGCCCCAGACAGCUUUGUACAUCUUGCGUGUGGGUGGGAACCCAAAAAGUUUCCUUUUCAGUGGAUCUGUUUAGGUGAGGUAAAGAAAUCCAUUACUCAAAUGUUUCAUCAGAGGCUACCCCCUGUUCAGGUGUGCACCCUGCACCCAUGUGGGUUUGCGGAUGGCAUAUAACACUUGCAGCAGCAGAGCUCGUUGCCACACAUCCAAGGGAAGUAAGUGUGCAUAUGUGGAUGCGGCGGGAAUACCUGCGGUCUUUCUGCUGAAGAGCAGGGUUAUACACCUCCUUUUAGCAAUCUGGAGAGGACUGAGGCAAGAGCUUGUAUUGAAACACAAGCAAGCUCCACGUAUGGUUUUGGACAUGGAAGAAAGAGUACUGUUGGGGUGGAAUGACCUAAGUUUUUAAUAGGAUUAGGAUUUCUGUGGAUUUUUCCCAAGUGAUAGAAGUUUUCUUCAUCUAGCAGGGAGCCUCACCCAAUUGCUUCUCUAUGUUCAUUUCUGAAACUCCUUUGUUAAAACUAAAUAGCAACAGAGAAGAAACUUUCUUCAAAAAACUCUUCAUAUCUGUCAUUUCUCCUAUUCUUAUGGAACUUCACAAUUGCUUUUUCUUUAUUCCUUUUUUUUUUUCUAUAUCAGCUCAUCAGUCUUUGUGGGUGACUUGGCUACCCCACUAAUCUAAUUGCCUUUUUGAUAGUUAAAUCAAUAUGGACAUCAACUUAAGGCUAUAUGUGAACCUUAAAUGCAUGAUAUUCCCUAUACUUGAUUCCACAAUUGAUAUUCUGUGAGGAAAGUUGGCCAGAUAUUCCCUUCUGUGAAGUCAGAAUAACUACCGACCCUAAGAAUAAACAUUUUGACCAAUUCUUUAUAUGUUGCAAACUAUUCACACAACUAGAAAGUUUAGCCAUUCACAUCUCUUCCCCUGAUUUUAAGUCCCAGAUUCUGAGACUCAGAAAGUUUAGUGACUUGUUGAGCUUUCUGUGGAAAAUCUGUUGUAAAAACAGUUCAGACAUUGGAAAAUAUAAAAUAGCCCCUAGAGAUCCCAAUAAAGCUUCCUCUCCCCAAAUCCCUCUACAAGUUUAUCCUCGAAAAACUUUCUGAAAACUGAUGAGAAAAUACUGAGUAAUUAAUGCUCAAAUGGGAAAGAUGACAUGUAAAAGCAAAAACCUGUUAAUGGCAUCUGUUCAUAUAGUUCCAUGUGCCUUUUUACUUAACUGCACUGAUAGGCAAUGUAAUGAAGAAGUUUCCUUUUAAAACGUAAAAUGUAAUUAAACAGAGUUUAUCUUAAAUUGGCUGGACCCGCACAGCUUGACUGAGACAUACACAGCUGUCUUCAUUUUGAAGCACCUACACUAGUCAAGCUUCUUUCUAACCCGCCCUUAGGGUUUGCCUGUUGGUCUGUCUUCCCUACUGGGCUGUUAAUCCCUUGGAGGCAGAUUGUCUUGUUUCCCAGAGUUUUUCCAGCAUAUACCAUGGCAGACAAUUUUCACCUUAUCUAUUCUAACUCGUAAGCCUCAGCUAGUGCCUCCAUCCUCGGGUGCAUAGCCCAGUGACAGGCAUGUAACAGACUUUGCCUACAAGCAGUUGCUGAUCCAUAAAUGACGUUGGCAACCUUCUUGUGGCAGUGAGUAACAUAUUUCUUUCCUCCUGAUAGGCUUGGAAUCCUCAUCCCCAUCUGGCAAUUUUCUUUCCAUCUUUCCUACACUCACAAUGGAGCCCACACGCCUCACAACCCCCUUGACUAAACCAGAUGACAGCAAGAAUGCCUAGUUCCAAGUGAGCAAGGGUGAAGCCUUAGGCCCUUGUCUCCUCCAGACCUCCUCUCUGCUCUAAGAGUAUACUGGGCAUGGGGUGUGGUCGGGGGGUUGGGGGCGGAGGAGUACUUAACCUCAAACUGAGAAAAAGGGUGUCCUGAGCAAGUUUCAUAGCGUAGCAGCUUCCAUUUGAAAUGUGAAGCUUUGAAGGCCUGUUGCUACAGUAACCAGCUAGCUCCUGACUCCAAUGCCUGUCUAAUCUAAGGUGGAAAUGUCCCAGAAACAGACCCCAGGCUGGCAGCUCUUAACUAUGACCCAUCUCAUAAGCACAUAUCCAGCUGUAGCCUCUUGGUUGCUGGGGUGAAGGGGCCUCUGUAUCGCCACAGGAAAAAAAAUCUGAUAAAUUACGGGCUCAAGAAGGGUGUUGCUUUUUUUUCCACUAACAGACUUUGCAACCCAGUUCCUGGUGAAAGGGCUCCGCACCCACCCGUUUUGUGUGUAUAAUGCUGAGCUAAAGUGGGAAGGAGCAGUAACACCAAAGGAGGCUAAUUCUCUUCCUGUCAGUAGGAGAGAGUGUCUGCCCCCAGUGUGUGAAAAGGGAAGGCAUGAGAAGUGAAAAAUCAGCCUUCUGGAAGCACCUUCUUACCACGAGAAAACAGGUGAUUCUUACUAUCUUUGAGACUCAUCCAGAUUGUGUCUGUUUAACUCUUCAGGCAAUAUGAAGGCAGAGAAGCCAUUUCAGAGAAGAGAUUUUUUAAAAAAUCAUUUCGUUCUUUGGCAUUGUCACAGGAUUAUGAUGUGGGUUCUCAUAAAAAUUUCACUCCCCCCAAAGCCACCCAAAGGAAAGGCAGUGAAAUGGGGAGGAACACACAUUUGCCUGGCAUCGCAAGAGCUGCCUUGUAGUCAUGGGUUCCAGUGAUCUUGGACCGAUCUCUUCACUUCCCUGGACCUCAGUUUCUUCCAUACAAAGAAGUUGAACUGGAUCAUAGAAAAGAUGCUGUCCAGCUUGGUAAUAUCAGAUAGGGAGCAGAAGCUGUCUCUUAGCACAUGGCCAGAUUCCGGAACAACGAUGAUGGUCUCCAUGUUUGUCCUAAAAAUGCAUCUCAUCUCAGUAGAGAUUUUCUUCCACCUCAUUUGGGUCUCAAUUUAAGGAAGGAAGAAAGGAAAGAAACCCGGGGAUUCUCUUCUUGAAAGGAAUAUACUUCACUUUCUCUAGGCUUCUAGGAUAAAAACUUCCUAUCCUUCAUUUUUCCUCUUUAAACCUGCCAAAAUCAAGUUGAGUAAAGAUACCAUACAGAUAUGAAAAAGAAGCCACAUCCUUAAAUUUUCAUGGAGUCCAAGAGCCUGCUCACCGCCAGUUAGCUUUUCCCAGGAUGGUGGUGGCACUGAUCAUCUAGGUUGCACUUUUAUGUUCAUGUCCCAGAGCGUUUCCCAUCAGCCAUCUCAUUUCAUCUUUUCAUCAUUCCUCUGAGGAAAAGACUUCACACAUGUAUAGGACUUUCUAUAUCACAAAGUAUUUCAUAUCCAAUGUCUUAUUUAGAUCUUGACAAUCACUGUUUAAGGUAAUUUGGCAAGUUAUUAAUACUCAUGUCCUCAUUUUACUGAAGAGGAAACUGAAAUGCAGAGAGCUUGUCUUUUGCCCAGGAUCACUCACCCAGUUUAUUGGGAGGCAGCAGCACGGGGAUUAAGAACAUGGGUUAUGCCGACAACCAACCAGGCAGAAUUCCAGCUCUGUCAGUAGUUAGCUGUCUGGCCUUAGGAAAGGGAUUUCACACCUCUGUGGCUUAGUUUCCUUGUCCAUUAAAUGCUCAUAAGAAUAGAGCUUUCCUCACAGAGAUUGGGUGGGCACGGGAGCUAAAUGAGCUCAUACGUUUAAGAACAACCUCUAGCACACAGUGCAUAAUAAAUGUCAUUAUUAUUAGCAAAGCCAGGACCUGGGUCUUCCAGCUUCUAGCUCAGUGGCAUUUCUGCUGCCCCACACCAGGACUAUCCUUCGUAUACAGGUAUGAACCUAAAGCCUUCAGUGUUUCAAUGAAAAGUUCACCCAAGGUCUUUCUGUUCAGUAAGUCUAGAGCUAAGGGCUCCUGGCACUCUGUUCAGUCCUUUCGCUGGUAAACCACGCUGCCCUCCGUUGCUCUGGGCAGAAUGUCAAACCUUCUUAUGUUUUUAAAAUUUAUAAAUCAAGCACUCUUAUUUAAUAUUACUGACAGCCCGAAGGCAGACGCUCCCACUCUCCUGGGGAAGAGGGUCUUCUAAUCUGCCAUCUUAAGGAGGUAAAAGGGCUUGAUUGGGUAACUCAUUGCAAUGGGCACGUAUUUAUUACUGUCUCCCGGCCUUUUCUCAUGCUGUUUGUCUGCUGGAAUUACCACUAGUGCCAGGCCAUUUGAAUAUUUGACCAUUUGUCUUAGAAUUCUCUGAAUACAAAUGUUUUUCAUACCUUUACUAUGUACUUUUUAAGAAUGAAGACUAUGUUGCAUGUUGGUUUGUACUCUCUCCUGCACAUAAAAAAUGCUUAGUAAAUAGAUACACAAAUGUU